AUGACAGAGUGUCUUUCUGUCCCCCAGGCUGGAGUUCAGUGGCAAGAUCUCGGCUCACUGCAACCUCUGCCUCCUGGGUUGAAGCGAUUCUCGUGCCUCAGCCUCCCGAGUGGCUGGGAUUACAGGCACGCACCACCAUGCCUGCCACUGUGCCUGGCAAUUUUUUUAUUUUUAGUAGAGACAGGGCUUCACCAUGUUGGCCAGGCUGGUCUUGAACUCCUGACCUCAGGUGAUCCACCCACCUCACAUGUGGAAAUUAAAUGCCGCAUCCUUAUAUUUUGCAGACAGGAUGUGAAAAGUUUAAGCAUGAGAAGUACAAAAAAGGGAACACUCAUAAAACAAUCCAAAUAA